GAUCUCAGCUCCUUUUCAGCUAGUGGGUGGAACCCCAGGAGGGAAAACUCAGGGAAGCCCAGGGCCCGUGUUGUGCUUUUGGCCCAGGUAGGUGGACAGACAUGUCCCAGGCGGGGGACGUAGAAGGCCCCAGCACAGGAGACCCUGUGCUCAGUCCCCAACACAACUGUGAGCUUUUACAGAACAUGGAAGGAGCCAGCUCCAUGCCAGGCCUGUCACCAGAUGGGCCGGGAGCAAGCUCUGGGCCCGGAGUCAGGGCUGGCAGCAGAAGGAAGAUCCCCAGGAAGGAGGCCCUUCGAGGUGGCAGCUCCCGGGCUGCAGGUGCUGCUGAGGUCCGGCCAGGGGUCUUGGAGCUGCUAGCUGUGGUACAGAGCCGGGGCUCGAUGCUGGCUCCUGGGCUCCACAUGCAGCUGCCCUCGGUGCCUACUCAGGGGAGAGCUCUGACCUCCAAGAGGCUCCAGGUUUCUCUGUGUGACAUCUUAGAUGACAGUUGCCCCAGGAAACUUUGUAGCAGGUCUGCUGGCCUCCCAGAGAGAGCUCUGGCCUGCAGGGAGAGGCUUGCAGGAGUGGAGGAGGUGAGCUGCCUCAGGCCCAGGGAGGCCAGAGACGGUGGAAUGAGUUCUCCAGGGUGUGACAGAAGAAGCCCCACACUCAGCAAAGAGGAGCCCCCUGGAAGGCCCCUGACAUCCUCACCAGACCCAGUCCCUGUGAGGGUAAGAAAGAAAUGGAGGAGGCAAGGGGCUCAUUCAGAGUGUGAGGAAGGGGCUGGUGACUUCCUGUGGCUUGAUCAGAGCCCUCGUGGGGACAACCUCCUGUCUGUGGGAGACCCUCCCCAAGUUGCUGACCUGGAGUCCUUGGGAGGCCCUUGCAGACCUCCCUCUCCAAAAGACACUGGGUCUGGGCCUGGAGAGCCAGGUGGAAGUGGGGCAGGAUGUGCCUCAGGGACUGAGAAAUUUGGAUAUUUGCCCGCUACAGGGGAUGGGCCCCAGCCAGGCAGCCCCUGUGGCCCUGUCGGGUUCCCAGUGCCCAGUGGAGGGGAGUCCCUCAGUUCAGCUGCACAGGCUCCUCCACAGAGCGCAGCACUGUGCCUGGGGGCGUCAGCACAGGCCUCUGCAGAGCAGCAAGAAGCUGUGUGUGUCGUGCGGACUGGCAGCGAUGAAGGCCAGGCUCCAGCACAGGACCAGGAGGAGCUGGAGGCCAAGGCUCAGCCAGCUUCCAGGGGAAGGCUGGAGCAAGGACUCGCUGCCCCCGCUGACACCUGUGCCAGCUCCCGGGAGCCCUUGGGCGGCCUCAGCUCCUCCCUGGAUACUGAAGCCAGCAGGGCCUGCUCAGGCCCAUUCAUGGAGCAGAGAAGAUCCAAGGGCACUAAGAACCUGAAGAAAGGUCCAGUGCCCUGUGCCCAAGACCGGGGCACAGACAGAAGCUCAGACAACUCCCACCAGGACAGGCCAGAGGAACCCAGCCCAGGAGGCUGCCCCAGACUGGAGGAAGUGAAAAUACCCCAUGGAGUGAAGCUUGUGUGCUACCUGGGUUCCGGGCCAGUGAUCCAGCUCCUGGGGGCCAUCAGCCACGGCCAGGCAGGGGGGCAGCUGCCACCAAAGCUGGAGGUUCUAGAGGACUUGAUGGAGGUCAGCUCACCCUCACCUGCCCAGAGGCUCAGAAGGAAGAAAAGGCCCAUGGUGCAGGGCCCUGCUGGGUGCCAGGUUUUCCAGCCUUCUCCUUCAGGAGGCACAGCAGGGGACCCUGGUGGCCUCUCUGACCCCUUCUACCCUCCAAGAAGCGGUUCCCUGGCCCUUGGCGACCCCAGCUCGGACCCUGCAUGUUCCCAGAGUGGCCCAAUGGAGGCUGAAGAGGAUUCUCUUCCGGAGCAGCCAGAGGACUCAGCUCAGCUCCAACAGGAGAAGCCAUCCCUGUAUAUUGGGGUGCGGGGCACUGUUGUCCGUUCCAUGCAGGAGGUACUAUGGACUCGCCUUCGGGAGCUCCCAGACCCAGUGCUGAGUGAGGAGGUGGUGGAGGGCAUUGCUGCUGGCAUUGAGGCAGCCCUCUGGGACCUGACACAAGGCACCAAUGGCCGGUACAAGACCAAGUAUCGCAGCCUGCUGUUCAACCUGCGGGACCCCAGGAACCUGGACUUGUUUCUCAAAGUGGUUCAUGGAGAUGUCACCCCCUACGACCUGGUGCGGAUGAGCUCGAUGCAGCUGGCCCCCCAGGAGCUGGCCCGCUGGCGGGACCAGGAGGAGAAAAGGGGCCUGAAUAUCAUUGAGCAGCAACAGAAGGAGCCGUGCAGACUUCCAGCCUCCAAAAUGACCCACAAGGGCGAAGUGGAGAUUCAGCGGGACAUGGACCAGACACUGACCCUGGAGGAUCUGGUGGGACCGCAGAUGUUCAUGGACUGCAGCCCACAGGCCCUGCCCAUCGCAUCAGAGGACACCACGGGGCAGCAUGACCACCACUUCUUAGACCCCAACUGCCACAUCUGCAAGGACUGGGAGCCCUCGAAUGAGCUGCUAGGCUCCUUCGAAGCCGCCAAGAGCUGCGGGGACAAUAUCUUCCAGAAAGCCCUAAGCCAAACUCCUAUGCCUGCUCCAGAGAUGCCCAAAACCAGGGAGUUGUCUCCCACGGAACCACAGGACAGGGUCCCUCCAUCUGGGCUCCAUGUGCCUGCUGCACCCACAAAGGCCCUGCCCUGCCUGCCACCCUGGGAAGGUGUUCUGGACAUGUUCUCCAUCAAGCGGUUCCGGGCCAGGGCCCAGCUGGUCUCGGGACACAGCUGUCGGCUUGUCCAGGCUCUGCCCACCGUGAUCCGCUCGGCAGGCUGCAUCCCCUCCAACAUUGUCUGGGACCUUCUGGCCAGCAUCUGCCCAGCCAAGGCCAAGGACGUCUGCGUGGUCAGACUGUGCCCACAUGGGGCCCGGGACACCCAGAACUGCCGCCUGCUCUACUCAUACCUCAAUGAUAGGCAGCGCCACGGGCUGGCCUCUGUGGAGCACAUGGGGAUGGUCCUGCUGCCCCUGCCUGCCUUCCAGCCCCUGCCCACCAGGCUGCGCCCUUUGGGGGGCCCAGGCCUUUGGGCUCUUCCUGUCUCCCCUCUCCUUUCCCCAGGUCUGGAGGUCACUCACUCAAGUCUGUUGCUGGCUGUGCUGCUCCCCAAGGAAGGGCUUCCAGACACAGCAGGGUCCAGCCCCUGGUUGGGGAAGGUUCAAAAGAUGGUCUCCUUCAACAGUAAGGUGGAGAAGAGAUACUAUCAGCCAGAUGACAGGAGGCCGAAUGUGCCCCUGAAGGGCACCCCUCCCCCAGGAGGUGCCUGGCAGCAGAGCCAGGGCAGGGGCAGUAUAGCUCCAAGGGGAAUCUCUGCUUGGCAGAGGCCCCCCAGAGGCAGGGGGAGGCUCUGGCCAGAGCCUGAAAACUGGCAGCAUCCUGGGCGAGGGCAGUGGCCCCCAGAGCCAGGCUUGCGCCAGUCCCAGCAUCCCUAUUCAGUAGCACCAGCUGGUCAUGGCUUUGGCCGUGGCCAGCACUUCCACAGGGACUCCUGUCCCCACCAAGCCCUGCUCCGGCACCUCGAAUCCCUGGCGACCAUGAGUCACCAGCUCCAAGCCUUACUGUGCCCCCAGACCAAGAGCUCCAUCCCCCGCCCUCUGCAGCGUUUGUCUAGCGCCCUUGCAGCUCCAGAGCCCCCUGGCCCAGCCCGUGACUCCUCUUUGGGGCCUACAGAUGAAGCUGGCUCUGAGUGUCCCUUCCCUAGAAAGGCCUGACCCUCCUUACCCACCAGAACAGGGGUUUUGAUGCCCUCACUAGUGUUGAAGCCUGUUCCAGAGAGAGGUGGGACUGCAAGGAGAGGAUGGUCAGCCCUACCCACCUGCCCUGUUUGAACUUCCUGUUUGACAAUGUUUGCUGUUGAUUUUUUGUUCAAUAAAGAAUUUGGUAAAAUUGGGA